AGCUGCGGCGCCUGCUGCUGCUGCUGCUGCUGCUGCUGCUGCUGCUGCGCGCUCUGCGCUGCCGCUGCGGCGGCUGCGGCCGCCGCGGCUGCGGCCGUGGCAAAGAAACAGGCUGCGGGCGGCAGGAAGGGCUGCUGGGGCUGCGGCUGGGGCUGCUGGCCGGCGCCGCCGCUCUCCAUCUUGGCAGAGCUUUCCAUGCGCAGCGGCGGCCAAGGAGUCGCGGAAUCAGAGCGAUCCGGGACGCGAGUGCGAGGUUAAAACCUUCAGCCCCACGUGCUGUUUGCAAACCUGCCUGUACCUGAGGCCCUAAAAAGCCAGAGACCUCACUCCCGGGGAGCCAGCAUGUCCACUGCGGUCCUGGAAAACCCAGGCUUGGGCAGGAAACUCUCUGACUUUGGACAGGAAACAAGCUAUAUUGAAGACAACUGCAAUCAAAAUGGUGCCAUAUCACUGAUCUUCUCACUCAAAGAAGAAGUUGGUGCAUUGGCCAAAGUAUUGCGCUUAUUUGAGGAGAAUGAUGUAAACCUGACCCACAUUGAAUCUAGACCUUCUCGUUUAAAGAAAGAUGAGUAUGAAUUUUUCACCCAUUUGGAUAAACGUAGCCUGCCUGCUCUGACAAACAUCAUCAAGAUCUUGAGGCAUGACAUUGGUGCCACUGUCCAUGAGCUUUCACGAGAUAAGAAGAAAGACACAGUGCCCUGGUUCCCAAGAACCAUUCAAGAGCUGGACAGAUUUGCCAAUCAGAUUCUCAGCUAUGGAGCGGAACUGGAUGCUGACCACCCUGGUUUUAAAGAUCCUGUGUACCGUGCAAGACGGAAGCAGUUUGCUGACAUUGCCUACAACUACCGCCAUGGGCAGCCCAUCCCUCGAGUGGAAUACAUGGAGGAAGAAAAGAAAACAUGGGGCACAGUGUUCAAGACUCUGAAGUCCUUGUAUAAAACCCAUGCUUGCUAUGAGUACAAUCACAUUUUUCCACUUCUUGAAAAGUACUGUGGCUUCCAUGAAGAUAACAUUCCCCAGCUGGAAGACGUUUCUCAGUUCCUGCAGACUUGCACUGGUUUCCGCCUCCGACCUGUGGCUGGCCUGCUUUCCUCUCGGGAUUUCUUGGGUGGCCUGGCCUUCCGAGUCUUCCACUGCACACAGUACAUCAGACAUGGAUCCAAGCCCAUGUAUACCCCCGAACCUGACAUCUGCCAUGAGCUGUUGGGACAUGUGCCCUUGUUUUCAGAUCGCAGCUUUGCCCAGUUUUCCCAGGAAAUUGGCCUUGCCUCUCUGGGUGCACCUGAUGAAUACAUUGAAAAGCUCGCCACAAUUUACUGGUUUACUGUGGAGUUUGGGCUCUGCAAACAAGGAGACUCCAUAAAGGCAUAUGGUGCUGGGCUCCUGUCAUCCUUUGGUGAAUUACAGUACUGCUUAUCAGAGAAGCCAAAGCUUCUCCCCCUGGAGCUGGAGAAGACAGCCAUCCAAAAUUACACUGUCACGGAGUUCCAGCCCCUCUAUUACGUGGCAGAGAGUUUUAAUGAUGCCAAGGAGAAAGUAAGGAACUUUGCUGCCACAAUACCUCGGCCCUUCUCAGUUCGCUACGACCCAUACACCCAAAGGAUUGAGGUCUUGGACAAUACCCAGCAGCUUAAGAUUUUGGCUGAUUCCAUUAACAGUGAAAUUGGAAUCCUUUGCAGUGCCCUCCAGAAAAUAAAGUAAAGCCAUGGACAGAAUGUGGUCUGUCAGCUGUGAAUCUGUUGAUGGAGAUCCAACUAUUUCUUUCAUCAGAAAAAGUCCGAAAAGCAAACCUUAAUUUGAAAUAACAGCCUUAAAUCCUUUACAAGAUGGAGAAACAACAAAUAAGUCAAAAUAAUCUGAAAUGACAGGAUAUGAGUACAUACUCAAGAGCAUAAUGGUAAAUCUUUUGGGGUCAUCUUUGAUUUAGAGAUGAUAAUCCCAUACUCUCAAUUGAGUUAAAUCAGUAAUCUGUCGCAUUUCAUCAAGAUUAAUUAAAAUUUGGGACCUGCUUCAUUCAAGCUUCAUAUAUGCUUUGCAGAGAACUCAUAAAGGAGCAUAUAAGGCUAAAUGUAAAACACAAGACUGUCAUUAGAAUUGAAUUAUUGGGCUUAAUAUAAAUCGUAACCUAUGAAGUUUAUUUUCUAUUUUAGUUAACUAUGAUUCCAAUUACUACUUUGUUAUUGUACCUAAGUAAAUUUUCUUUAAGUCAGAAGCCCAUUAAAAUAGUUACAAGCAUUGAACUUCUUUAGUAUUAUAUUAAUAUAAAAACAUUUUUGUAUGUUUUAUUGUAAUCAUAAAUACUGCUGUAUAAGGUAAUAAAACUCUGCACCUAAUCCCCAUAACUUCCAGUAUCAUUUUCCAAUUAAUUAUCAAGUCUGUUUUGGGAAACACUUUGAGGACAUUUAUGAUGCAGCAGAUGUUGACUAAAGGCUUGGUUGGUAGAUAUUCAGGAAAUGUUCACUGAAUAAAUAAGUAAAUACAUUAUUGAAAAGCAAAUCUGUAUAAAUGUGAAAUUUUUAUUUGUAUUAGUAAUAAAACAUUAGUAGUUUAAACAAUUUCACUGUUUCAGUUAUUUCCUGGAAUGAAAUAUUCCUCUCACUGCCUUAGAAAUACAUUAGCUAGAUAGUUUUGUAACAUGAGAAAAUGGCCAGAGGCUCAUAUCUCCAACCCUUUGCAGGGGCUCCUUGUGACACUCAAAGUCAUGCCUGGACAGUCAACGGACUUUGACUUUUGUUGAUUGUGUGUUUGCCAUGAAAACAUGAAUAUCUGAGAAGCAGUGGGGAGAAAAAAAACAAUAUCUUUGUAGCUAUGAUUUGAAAUUCUCAUACUACUUUACAUUUUAUUUUGGAAAUAGUUAAGUCUUAAAGAAUUUGCAUAGUGUUUCUUUGAGUUUAGUUCUCAGAACAGCUGUAGUAUCAUCAACAGCAAAUUCUGGGUACCUUCCCAGCUCCACCCAAUUUGAAUCUCUGAAGAUAAGGCCCAGAGACCUGUAUUUUUAAGUACCCCAUUUUUUUAAUUAUUCAUAGCCAAAUUCUAUCAGGUACAUUCAGUUUGAGAAAACCUGAUUUGUGGUGGUCAGUCUGCCACUGCCAAUGAUGUCAAUGUGGAUAAGCUGUUUCCCUUCUUUAGACCUCAGUGUCACUCUAACAAUGAGGGAGUUAAACUUUAUAAACCAAGGUCCAUUGCAGCCUUGAAAUAUGAUUCAAGUGUUCAUAUGUGUCUUUAUAUAGCUAUGCCUGAUCCACUGAUGGGGUGUUACAAUACCUGCUUAUAUAUGCCAGCUGGGAGGAAAGAGGAAUUUACUGAAUGUGUCUGAAGUUUCAUUGUUUUGAAGUUGGAAUUUUAUGCCUGUAUCUAUGUUUAUGCCUUUGUAAAACCCACUGAUUUUAAAAGUGAAAAAGGACUUUUUUCUCUGCUUUUACUCUAAACACCAAACAAUCCCUGCAAAGGGAUUAUUCUGAUGUUUCUUCAUUUCACAUGAAAAGUUAAUUAUUGACUCUGGAACUUAAAUAUUAGAUAAUAUUUUUGACAAUAUUGAAGAGUGAGUUUUAGUCCAGUAAAGAUGUUUUAAUGAGCUUGAAGGUAAAGUUUCGGUUAAGUUAUGAUUUUCACAGGAAGUUACAUACUGAAUGAAAGAUAAUAUUUGUAUUUUUGGUAAUGUGCUACUCAGUUCUUAGCUCUUUUUUAUCCAGAUAUAAAAGCCCAGUCUAUAGCUAUGGGAUUUAAUAAAUUUCCAAUAUGUAAGUGUUUUUAUUUGUUUAAUUUCUAGUAAAUGAGCAAUAUUUUAGAAACAGUAUCAGUCUUUACUGACAGAUGAUCUUGCUGAGUACAAUCAAAAUAAAUACAUAAAAAAUUCUAAGCAUGUGGCAUUGAUGUUUAAUAAGUUUCUGAAAGUAGGAAUCUGAAUUUUAACUGUAGGUUUCUAAGUUAUAUAAUUUAGUUGUGUUUCAAAAAAUCCACCAAUAAAAUGUCAGCUUUAUAAAAACA